AGAGUAGAAACAGUUCCUUAUAUUAAGACAGAUGAAUUUGCUACCUCUUCCCUCUUCAUGAAUUUUUUUUAAAUGUAUGGUUGUAUAUCCUUCCAGUUUUAUAAUCACAUUUGAAAACUCAACCAUCUUUCUGGGCACAAUUUGAUGGCUGAAGAUAUGCUUCACUCCAAUAAAAAGAAAAUGAAGAUUUUUCAAGAGCAUUCGUAGGCUUCGAAUCAAAAGGACAGUACUUAUUUCCUGAGGUCUGAUAACCGUUGUUUUAUGAGGAAAUAGUACUAGGAUCACAGUACCAUGGAUGUGGUAGGCGAAAAUGAGGCCCUGCAGCAGUUCUUUGAAGCUCAGGGAGCCAAUGGUACUCUGGAGAACCCAGCCCUGGACACAAGUCUGUUGGAGGAAUUUCUGGGCAAUGACUUUGAUUUGGGGGCCUUGCAACGCCAGCUCCCAGACACCCCGCCCUAUUCUGCAUCCGACUCAUGCUCUCCUCCGCAGGUCAAAGGUGCAUGCUACCCAACCCUGAGGCCCACAGCUGGGAGGACUCCAGCUCCUUUUCUCCACCCCACAGCUGCUCCUGCGAUGCCGCCCAUGCACCCGCUGCAGAGCACCUCUGGAAUGGGCGACUCCUGCCAAAUCCACGGAGGCUUUCACAGCUGCCACUCAAACGCCAGUCAUCUUGCCACCCCCCUGGACCAAUCCGUGUCCUCCCAUCUGGGGAUAGGUUGUUCUUACCCUCAGCAGCCUCUGUGUCACAGCCCUGGAGCCUCAUUGCCUCCAACCAAGAAGAGAAAGUGCACGCAGGCACUGGAGGACUCCGGGGAAUGCCGAGUGUGGGCCUGCCACUGCAGACCGAUGACAAGUAGGAGUCGCAGCAGUGAAGUCCAGGACCCUGACAGUGAGGGACAGAACAGAAUGCCUACAGACCAGUGCUCUCCUGCUCUGAAGUGGCAACCAUGCCAUAGUGUUCCUUGGCACAGCUUAUUAAACAGUCAUUAUGAAAAACUACCUGAUGUGGGCUAUCGAGUUGUAACAGACAAAGGAUUUAAUUUUUCACCAGCAGAUGAAGCUUUUGUUUGCCAAAAGAAGAAUCAUUUCCAGAUAACCAUUCACAUCCAAGUUUGGGGAAGUCCAAAAUUUGUUGAAACCGAGAUGGGCCUAAAGCCAAUAGAAAUGUUUUACUUGAAAGUUUUUGGCACUAAGGUGGAAGCUACCAAUCAAAUAAUUGCUAUUGAACAGUCCCAAGCAGAUAGGAGCAAAAAGAUUUUCAAUCCUGUUAAAAUUGACCUACUGGCUGACCAGGUCACCAAAGUAACACUGGGACGAUUACACUUCAGCGAAACCACAGCAAAUAAUAUGAGAAAAAAGGGAAAACCAAAUCCAGACCAGAGAUACUUCAUGUUGGUGGUUGGACUGUAUGCUGCUAACCAAGACCAGUUCUAUCUGUUGUCUGCCCACAUCUCUGAAAGGAUCAUUGUAAGGGCCUCUAACCCUGGGCAGUUUGAAAAUGACAGUGAUGCAUUGUGGCAGCGAGGACAAGUUCCAGAAUCUAUUGUCUGUCACGGUCGAGUAGGAAUCAACACAGAUGCGCCGGACGAAGCCCUGGUUGUCUGUGGCAACAUGAAAGUGAUGGGGACCAUCAUGCAUCCCUCUGACAGCCGGGCAAAGCAGAAUAUCCAGGAGGUUGACACGAAUGAACAGCUGAAAAGAAUAGCCCAAAUGAGAAUUGUUGAAUAUGACUACAAACCUGAAUUUGCAUCUGCAAUGGGAAUAAACACUGCCCAUCAAACAGGAAUGAUUGCCCAGGAGGUGCAAGAAAUCCUGCCCAGAGCAGUAAGAGAGGUUGGUGAUGUCACCUGCGGAAACGGAGAGACCUUGGAGAACUUCCUCAUGGUGGAUAAGGACCAGAUCUUUAUGGAAAAUGUAGGUGCAGUGAAGCAACUGUGCAAACUAACUAACAACCUUGAGGAAAGAAUAGAAGAGUUAGAAAUAUGGAACAGAAAGCUGGCCCGGCUAAAGCGGCUCAGUAGUUGGAAGUCAUCAGCCAGUGAAGCAAGCACAAUCAGCAAAUCUAGCAGAGCCGUUAGUGCAUCUUCUCCAAGAAGGGCCGUUCAUAAAAAAAACAACAAGGUUUAUUUUUCAGGAAAAAGACAGGCGUGUCCUAAUUGGGUUUUCCAGACCUUGGUUAUAACUCUGAUUGCUGUGAUGGCAUUUUGUGCUUUGACGAUAGUUGCCCUCUAUAUACUUAGCUUAAAAGAUCAAGACCGACGUGUCCCAAAUCUCCCUCCAAGCAAUAUCACAAGCUCACAGGAGCCAGCUCUGCUGCCCACAGCCUCCUCCUCAGCACCUAAUACAUCCCUGGUAACCACACCGGCCUCCUUACAAGUACCUGAAAUUACUUUCUGUGAAAUCCUGCCGUGUCAGGAGACUUAUUGCUGCCCCAUCCGGGGAAUGAAAGAAGUCUCUUCAAGUCCUGUGCAAAGACAAUCUGAGGAGAAGGAAUUCCAUCAGAGGCGAUGGUCAGAAGACAAAAGCAAAUCAGUUUUGGCAAGAAAUGCACUCAGCGGCCCUGACUGGGAGAGUGACUGGAUUGAUACAACCAUCAGUUCUAUUCAGAUUAUGGAAAUCCAGCAAAUAAUAGAUCAUCAGUAUUGCAUUCAAAGCCUCCAGUGCGGAUCUGGAAAUUAUAAUUACAAUAUUCCUGUUAAUAAACACACACCCACCAAUGUCAAGUUCUCUCUGGAAAUAAACACAACAGAGCCAUUGAUAGUCUUCCAGUGCAAAUUCACCCUUGGAAAUAUAUGUUUCCAUAGUAAAAGGGGAACCAAAGGGCUGGAAAGCCACAGAGAAAUCUCCCAGGAGAUGACACAGGGAUAUCAGCACAUUUGGAGCCUCCCUGUAGCCCCAUUUUCUGACAGCAUGUUCCAUUUCCGUGUAGCUGCACCGGAUUUAGCUGACUGUUCAACUGAUCCUUAUUUUGCUGGGAUAUUCUUCACCGAUUACUUCUUUUACUUCUAUCGACGCUGUGCCUAAUUUGUUCAAGUUUGGGGACUUUACCAAAGAAAAAUACUCAGGAAUACAUUUAACAGAAACGAACAUCCUCUUGCAACUUCUUUUUUCUUCUUUGUAAAACAUUUACGUUUAUUGCUGAAGGACUUUUUCAGGCUUUAGCUUCCAACAGUUUUGAGACAUUAAUGAGGAGAAUAAAAUGUUUGCUGAAACUUGAAAUAAUGUGAUGUUUGAUUUUGCCAUGACUAUGAAGAAAACAUUUCCUGGAGCAAACAGUUCUGUUGAAUUUAAAAAUACUAUUAUUUCUGGUAUUAAGGAAGUUGUGAGCUCAAAAUAAGGAGAUCUAGCCUCUAUUUUGUUUUAAUGUAUUUUAAAGCUUUUGAAAAAACCAAAAGGGCCAUGUCGACUUCGGCCCACUAAACAUAGACUCUUGAGAAUGUGUGAUAUGGUAUGUGGAGGAGAUGUGGGGGGUGGUAUCUGAUACUGAGCUCACAUUUAGGCAAAUUGUCCUAUGUGUGUGUGUAUUGUAUAAACACAUACACUAGAGUACAGAAUGUAGUUUGUUAAUCAAAUGGAUUUAAGAGAAAUAA